AGAGGGCCUUGGGGCACAGUCCAAUGAGGAGCGAGCCGGGUGGCCGGCUGAGGGGCGUGCUUCAUGCUCGCGGGAUUUUUAAAAAUGGUUUCUCCUGGAUCUUAUCCCAACUGCGCCUGAGACCUUGUUUCACCUCCUGAUGUGCUGGGUGUGGUUAGGCCUCGAGCCGGGAGCUAUUUGCCUCCCAGGAGGAAGCCAGGGCAGGGUUCCGCGGGGAAUGGCGGUGAGGGAGCCACUCGGGACGCGGAGGCCCUAAAAUGAAGAAGCUUCGGCCUGAGGCUUCGGGAGCGGCGAGCAGGGAAGUGGGAGUGUGUGUGAGUGUGUGUGUGUGUGUGUGUGUGUGUGUGUGAAUAAGCCAGAGGCUGCCUGGUGGGGCCCCGCCGUGGCCCAGUGACUGAGAUAAUUGUCUUCGUCUGUGGGGUAAUGCGAACAAGCCCCGUUCCCCUAAGCCGUGAUGCAUGCGGGGUUGACGCGGCCGGGCUCUGUCCCCAUAAACUGUGACACAGGUGUGUGUAGACGUCUAUGAGGGCCAUAGCGCCGGGCUGUAAGGGCAUCUGUAGGGGUGACGCAGCCGGGCUGUGUCUCUGCACCUCCGUUCUGUGCGAGGUCAAUGCUGGUGGGGUCUGCAGAGGUGGCACGGCCAGGACGGGUCUCCGUGUCUCUGAAAUGUGCCUUUGCACUUCUGUCAGGUUGACAGGGACAGGCAGUGUCCCUCUGGUGUGAGCGUCUGUGGGUGUGAAAGGGCCAGCGAGUGUGCGGCUGUGACUGGUCGGGAUCGGGCCUGGGUGCAUGGCCUUUUGAGUGAGCACAGGUGUGUGCGACCAUGUCACCUGUCUUUCUAGUGUCUCCGUUGCUUCCUGUGCCUUGGCCUUCCAGCCAUGUGGUACCUGCUAGGGAGCAGUGGUCCCAAAGUGACGUGAGAGGCUCUACGCUAUUGUGAAAAUGACCAAGAAGAAGGCUUCACAAGUCACGAGAUGGCAGUUUUGGAGCCAGAAGUGCUCUCCGUGCACACUACCUGGACGACAAGAGGAAGUAACCUCAAGAAUAGAAUUCCUUUUGGGGAAGAAAGAGCUGGCCUUCAGGAAAAGCAUCCCGGAGGAGGAAGAAGAAGUGUUAUAUGUCCUAAAGUAAGGUUUCAGCAAGCAAGGGACACCGAAUAGCAGCUCCGGCAGCCUGUGCUAGCGGCCUGCAGAGAAUUCCAGGUGACGCUCCAGAGGGGCUAGGAGAGGAUACCCUUCUGAGGACAGCCAUGGCUCGCCCGGCAUCACCCCACUCAAGAGGCCAGACGGGGUCCCAGCUGGGGUGACACAGCUCCUUUCCCAGUCGGGAAGGGGCGUCUGCAGGGACCAGGAAGGGCUUAGCUUGGGGCUGCCCGCUCCGGCACCGACCUGGGACGCGCCCUGAGGCCCCUGCCUGGGACCGUCCCGGACUACAUUUCCCAGAGACCAUCCAGGAGUACGCCGUGCUGCAUGCUGGAACACGGGGCUUGGGGCUCUGGUUUCCCCCGACGGCCCCGCGUCCUCUUCUAGCCUCACCCUCUCCCGAGGCCCCAGCGUUGGGGGACUACCGGGUGCGUCUGCGGCUUUGGGAGAGUGGGAGGAGGGAAAGGGAUGGGAGGGGUGCACGCACACGUGUCAGUGUGUCCGCGUGUCAGCAUCUGUGCAGGCGCACGUGUGUGUCGGGCUCUGUUGUGUCUGCACAUGCGUGUCGGCAUCUGUGCGUGCGCACACGCCCGUCAGGGUCUGUGUGCCCGCACAGGCACGUCAACAGCUGAGCACGCUAUGUAUCGGGGGUCUGUGUACGCUCACAUACGUGUCGGGGUCUGGGUACGUGCACAUACGUGUAGGGGUCUGUGUGCACAUGCGUGUCGGGCUCUGCUGCUGUCUGCGCGCUGCGGCCGCUGGGUGCGCGUGCGCAUGCGCGCUGGCCUCCAGGGGGUGGCGGGACCGAGUGUGUGACGCACUUGCGUGGGAGUACGAGGCUGACGCGGCGGCCCUGUCCCCGUAACUGUGACACGGGUGCACGCGAGCGUCAUUGGGGGCGAUGGGGGCCGUGCUGGGUGCGCGUUUGCACCAGUGACGCAGCCGCUGCAUCUCCGCCAGUCCGCGCAGGUGAGAUUGGUGCGCGUGGCUCCGAGGGGAGACGGGCACGGGGCUUCUGACGGUGACGCACUUGCUGGAGAGUGUGGGGUGACACAGCCGGGCUCUCCCCAUAACUGGUGACCGGGGGUGCUCCAGAGGCUUUGGGUCAACGCAGCCCGUGCCUGUGAACCUCGGCGGUGCGUCCCUGGGACUCUGCUCCGUGAGGUGCGCUCUGGGGGUUGUGCGGGGGCAGCGGUCGGGACGGGUCUCCGUGGCCCACGGAUGCACCUCUGCACCGUGUGGGGUGGUGGGGCCCGUAGCAUGGCCGUGCUGGGCGUUAGUGGGUAUGAGGGGCGCAGAUGUGUCUCAGGACAGAGUGAGCUGUGGUGAGGCUGAGCUGUGCAGACUUGUGCUGGGAUGGGUGAUCGGGCCUUCUGGGUGACGCAGGUGUGUGUGACAACACAACCUGUAGCUUCAGCGUCUCUGUGCUGGGAUGGAUGAUCGGGCCUUCUGAGUGAUGCAGGUGUGUGUGACAGUGCAACUUGUAGCUCCAGCGUCUCUGCUGCUUCCCCUGCCUUCACCUCCUAACCAAGCGGUACCUGCCUGAGAACAAGGGCCGCGGAGGGACGUGAGCGCCUGAGCCUCGCCUGGAAAUUCACCAGCAAGAAGGCAGAAACAGCCAUGAGGCCAGCAUCCUUCAGAAAAAGCAUCCCCGAGGAGGAAGACGAAUCGUUAAACAUCUGAAAGGGUCAGGCCAGCAUCCUUCAGAAAAAGCAUCCCCGAGGAGGAAGACGAAUCGUUAAACAUCUUAGGUCAGCUUUACCAGUGAGGAAACCGACACUGUGAGCUCUAGCCUCUCGGAAUUUGUCUUCUUCAGUGGAAACCCCGAGAAGACUGAUCAGUUCUUCAGUUCUAAAACAAUGGCCCAGGGUUUGGUGACGUUCGCCGACGUAGCCAUAGACUUUUCUCAGGAGGAGUGGGCCUGUCUGAACUCUGCUCAGAGGGACCUGUACUGGGACGUGAUGCUGGAGAACUACAGUAACUUGGUCUCACUGGAUUUGGAGUCAGCAUAUGAAAAUAAGAGUUUACCUACAGAAAAAAACAUUCAUGAAAUAAGGGCUUCCAAAAGGAAUUCAGAUAGAAGAAGUAAAUCCCUUGGCCGUAACUGGAUAUGUGAAGGUACGCUUGAAAGACCACAGCGCUCCAGAGGGAGGUAUGUCAAUCAGAUGAUCAUCAAUUAUGUCAAAAGACCUGCUACUAGAGAAGGCACCCCUCCUAGAACACAUCAGAGACAUCAUAAGGAGAAUUCCUUUGAAUGUAAGGACUGUGGGAAGGCCUUUAGUCGUGGCUAUCAACUUAGUCAACAUCAGAAAAUCCAUACUGGUGAGAAACCUUAUGAAUGUAAAGAAUGUAAGAAGGCCUUCCGUUGGGGCAAUCAGCUUACUCAACAUCAAAAAAUUCAUACUGGGGAGAAGCCCUACGAAUGUAAAGACUGUGGGAAGGCUUUUCGAUGGGGCUCAAGCCUCGUUAUUCAUAAGAGGAUUCAUACUGGUGAAAAACCCUAUGAAUGUAAAGACUGUGGAAAGGCCUUUCGGCGUGGUGAUGAGCUCACUCAGCACCAGAGAUUCCACACUGGGGAGAAAGACUACGAAUGCAAAGACUGUGGGAAGACCUUUAGCCGUGUGUAUAAACUUAUUCAGCACAAGAGAAUUCAUAGUGGGGAGAAGCCUUACGAGUGUAAAGACUGUGGGAAGGCUUUUAUUUGUGGUUCAAGCCUCAUUCAGCAUAAAAGAAUUCACACAGGUGAGAAACCCUAUGAAUGUCAAGAAUGUGGGAAGGCCUUUACUCGAGUCAAUUACCUUACUCAGCAUCAGAAGAUCCACACCGGUGAGAAGCCUCACGAAUGUAAGGAGUGUGGGAAGGCCUUUCGCUGGGGUUCGAGCCUCGUUAAGCACGAGAGGAUACAUACGGGCGAGAAGCCGUACAAGUGCACAGAAUGUGGGAAGGCCUUCAAUUGUGGCUAUCACCUCACUCAGCACGAGAGAAUCCACACAGGCGAAACCCCGUAUAAAUGUAAGGAGUGUGGGAAGGCUUUCAUUUAUGGAUCGAGCCUCGUGAAACAUGAGAGAAUUCAUACCGGGGUGAAACCCUAUGGGUGUACAGAAUGUGGGAAGAGCUUUAGUCACGGCCAUCAGCUUACACAACAUCAGAAAACGCACAGUGGGGCGAAAUCCUACGAAUGUAAGGAGUGCGGGAAGGCAUGUAACCACCUAAACCAUCUCCGAGAACAUCAGAGGAUCCACAACAGUUGAAGAGCCUUUUGAACGCAGUAGCCCGCUCGUAUCUAUGGUUUCGCUUUCCACAGUUUGUUACCUGCAGUCAACUGCAGUUCAAAAAUAUUAAAUGGAAAAUUCCAGAAAUAAAGAAUUUUAAGUCUCAAAUGGUGUGCCCUUCUGAGUAGCGUGAUGAAAUCUCUCGCUGUCCGGCUCCAGCCGGCCGGGGAUGUGAGUCAUCCCUUGGUCCAGCACAUCCACGCUGUAUACGCCACCCACCCUGCUAGUGACUUAGUAGCCGUCUUGGUGAUCAGAUCAACUAUCCCAGCAUCACAGUGCCUGUGCCCAAGCAGUCCUCACUUUGCUUAACAGUGGCCCCAGAGAGCAGGAGUAGUGAUGCUGGUGAUUCGGAUAUGCCAAAGAGAAGCCACAAAGUGCUUCCUUUUAAAUGAAAAGGUGAAAGUUCUCAACUUAAAAAAGAAAAGAAAAAAAUCAUAUACUGAGGUUGCUAAGAUCUACAUGACAAUAAGAUAUUUUGGGAGAGAGAUACGUUCACAUAAUUUUAUUACAUAUAUUGUUACAAUUGUUCUAUUUUGUUAGUUACUGUUGGUAAUCUCUUACUGUGCCUAAUUUAUAAAUUAAACUUUAGAUAUGUAUGUACAGGAAAAAAUGUAGUAUAUAGUAUCGUAUAUAUGUACAGGAAAAAAACGUACUAUCUGUGGUUUCAGGUGUCCACUGCGGGUCUUCAAACGUACCCCCCUCAGGUGAGAGGGGACUGCUGUACAAAGAAUAUAGGAAGGCCUCUAGACUACAUCCAUUCCUUCCUCAACAGGAGGAAAAUUCCUGGUACAGUUUAACGUAAGGCUUCACUGAUCACUGUUGUUUUUGUUUUUGUUUUUGUUUUUUUGAGACAGAGUCUCACUCUUGCCCAGGCUGGAGUGCAGUGGCACGGUCUUGGCUCACUGCAACCUCCACCUCCCAGGUUCCAGCAAUUCUCCUGCCUCAGCCUCCCCAGUAGCUGGGAUUACAGACAUGCACCACCACACCUGGCUAAUUUUUGUAUUUUUAGUAGAGACAGUUUUCACCAUGUUGUCCAGGCUGGUCUCAACUCCUGACCUCAGGUGAUCCACCCACCUUGCCCUCCCAAAGUGCUAGGAUUACAGGCGUGAGCCACUGCACCUAGCCCACUGAUCACUCUUCUGCUUACAGAAUAUCAGAAGUCAUUCUAGAGGCAAAUUUGAAGAGUGGAAAAAUCACUUUUUCUGAAUGAUCUUGUUUUUGGUGUAGAUGUUUUUAUUGUGUGGGUUAGUUUAAUGAAUACAUAAAGACUACCAGUACCAUUCUGUCUUUACUCCGUGGCAUCUGUGGAAUAACCCUGCUAAUGUAACACGUGAGAAAGCCUUUGGUCAUGCCACCCACUCUACCAGUUGUCCCCACCAUCCCCCGCCCUCCUCCCUGUGAGACACUGGGCCAAAGGCUCACUACCCCUGUGCGUUGUCCAGCACACAGACACUAUGUGCAUUAUUUGUACAUAAGGAUAAUCACAUCUACCUGAGACUGCUAUCAUGGAAAUUAAAUGUUUGGUACAUGUAAAGUCUUUGAAAGUGUAACUGGAAUAUUGUGUAAUUUUAAUAAAUAAUAACUAUUGUUGUUUUUAUGAUCAUUACUACCAUUUGUGUUGCCAUUAGUGAAUUUUUACAAGAAAACUCCCUGUGGGUGCAAUGAGUCUGGAAAAGACCAUUGAGUCUUCUAGAAGAAAACAUUAAGAGAUUAUUGGCACAGCCGUGGGUUACGCAAUGAUUUCUUAGUACACAAAACACAGCAAACAUAAAAAGUUGUUACACUUCAUCAAAAGUACAAAGUUCUGUUCAUCAAAUGAUGCUGUUAAGAUAGGGAAAAGACAAGAAACAGGACUGGAAGAAGAUGUUUGCUCUAAGGUACACCUGACAAAGGAACUCUCAUAGAAAAUAUAAAGAAUCCCUCAAGUUGAAAAAAAAAUCAAUUUAAAGGGGAGAAAACUUCAGCACGUCUCAACAGAAGACCACCAAAUGGCCAAUAAGUAAGUGAAAAUGUAUUCAAUGUCAUUGCUCCUCAAGGAACUGUAGAGUAAAACCACAAUGUGCUGUCACUCUAGACAGUCACCAGGAUGAUUAAAUUUAAAUCACAAUAACAAGGCUGAUUUCAGAUGUCUCACCACAAAGAAGGAGGAUAAGGGAGCGAGGUGAUGGAUAUGUUAAUUAGCUUGAUUUAAUCCUUCCACAUUGUAUACAUGUAUCAGAACAUCACAUUGUACUCCAUCAAUAUAAUACAAUUAUUAUUUGUCAAUCAAAUAUUAAUAAAAUCAAAGAUGAGCAGG